ACCCCAGGAAGAGAUGCAGGAGGCGAUUUUUACCUCAGAUGUUGAAAUUUACACUGCUUUGAAAGAAAGAAGAUAUGUUUUCAGCAUUGAAAUAUCAUGCAAUAGACUAUUUAUAUGAGAAUGUGGUUAGAAAGAAGUUUUACAGAGAUGCUUUAUUGCUUCGAAUCCCUUCAUGUUUAUAUCAAGAUGAAAGUUACCAUGUAGCAGUUACUGAUAAUAAAUUUAGGAGGCCAUGGACGAGAGUCUCAGCUGUUUCAGUUCCGGGAAUGACAGAUACCUCAGUCUUGGACCAAUGGAAAGCAAGUUUCUUUGUGGAGGAUUUCCUUGAGAAAAAAACAAUUACAAGAAUGGUGACCCAGAUUAAUUGUGAAUUUGAGGAAGUUGUUCCAAGUUCAAAUCCAGACUCCCAAAUUGAAGUAGAGGAGGUCAGUUUAUACACCCACAUGGACUACAAUGAAGUCUUUACCCCUGUCAGUUGUUUAGAAAAAUGUUCAGCACUUCAAAACCAGAACCAAGAUUUAUUUAUUGAUGAUAAAGGAAUACUUUUUGUAAGUAGUAGAAAACACCUACCAACUUUGCCUACUCUCUUGAGUAGACUAAAACUGUUUUUGGUAAAGGAUCCUCUUUUAGAUUUCAAAGGACAGAUCUUCACAGAAGCUAAUUUUUCCAGGGAAUGUUUCUCUCUUCAAGAAACUUUGGAAGCUUUUGUGAAAGAAGAUUUUUGUAUGGAUAAAGUGAACUUUUGUCAAGAGAAACUAGAAGAUACAAUAUGUUUAAAUGAGCCGUCAAGUUUUCUUAUUGAGUAUGAAUUCUUAAUACCUCCAAGCCUCAAACCAGAAAUUGAUAUUCCAUCACUCUCAGAACUGAAGGAGUUAUUAAACCCAGUGCCAGAAAUAAUAAACUAUGUAGAUGAAAAGGAAAAGCUUUUUGAAAGAGAUCUUACUAACAAGCAUGGAAUUGAGGAUAUCGGGGAUAUAAAAUUCAGCUCCACAGAGAUUUUGACCAUUCAAAGCCAGAGUGAACCAGAAGAGUGCAGUAAACCAGGAGAGUUAGAAAUGCCACUAACUCCUCUAUUCCUAACAUGCCAACAUUCUUCAGUGAAUUCAUUACGUACAGAACUUCAGACAUUUCCAUUAUCUCCGGUUUGUAAAAUUAAUUUGCUUACUGCUGAAGAAUCAGCUAAUGAAUACUACAUGAUGUGGCAAUUAGAAAGAUGUAGAAGCCCUUUGAACCCAUUUUUGCUUACAGUGCCAAGAAUUCAAGAGCCCCACAGCCAAUAUUCAGUUACAGAUUUGAAAAAGAUAUUUUCUGUUAAAGAAGAAAGCCUUGUGAUUAAUCUGGAAAAGGCAGAGUGGUGGAAACAAGCAGGACUAAAUCUGAAAAUGAUGGAAACAUUGGAACAUCUGAAUACAUAUUUAUGUCAUGAUAAUUUGUCUUCUAAUGACACUAAAAUUGAGAUAUUUUUGCCUACGAAAGUGCUUCAAUUAGAAUCAUGUCUAGAACAUAAAAGUCAUUCUUCACCUAUUGCACUUAUUGAUGAAAAAUCUACAAAUGCUCAUUUAUCACUUCCACAAAAGAGUCCAUCUCUGGCAAAAGAAGUACCAGAUCUAUGUUUUUCUGAUGACUAUUUCUCUGAUAAAGGAGCAGCAAAAGAAGAAAAACCAAAGAAUGACCAAGAACCAGUAAACAGAAUAAUCCAAAAGAAAGAAAAUAACGAUCACUUUGAACUUGACUGCACAGGACCAUCUAUUAAAUCACCUUCCUCUUCAAUAAUUAAAAAAGCAUCUUUUGAACAUGGCAAAAAACAAGAGAAUGAUUUGGACCUUUUGAGCGACUUUAUUAUGCUGCGAAAUAAAUAUAAGACUUGCACCUCAAAGACUGAAGUCACAAACAGUGAUGAAAAACAUGAUAAAGAAGCAUGUUCUUUGACACUUCAAGAAGAAAGUCCUAUUGUUCAUAUUAAUAAAACCCUGGAGGAAAUAAAUCAGGAAAGGGGAACAGAUAGUGUCAUUGAAAUUCAAGCGUCAGAUAGCCAGUGCCAAGCAUUUUGCCUCCUCGAAGCAGCAGCUUCUCCUAUCUUAAAAAACCUUGUAUCCUUGUGUACCCUCCCUACUGCUAAUUGGAAAUUUGCCACUGUUAUUUUUGACCAAACAAGGUUUCUCUUAAAGGAACAAGAAAAAGUAGUAAGUGAUGCUGUUCGCCAAGGUACAAUUGAUGAAAGAGAAAUGACUUUCAAGCAUGCCGCUCUCUUACAUCUUCUGGUAACAAUUAGAGAUGUCCUUUUAACAUGCAGCUUGGACACAGCAUUGGGAUAUUUGUCGAAGGCAAAAGAUAUCUACAACAGCAUUUUAGGCCCCUAUUUGGGUGACAUUUGGAGACAGCUGGAGAUUGUACAGUUUAUUAGGGGGAAAAAGCCUGAAACCAACUACAAGAUACAAGAAUUGCAAUGUCAGAUACUAAGUUGGAUGCAAAGUCAACAGCAAAUUAAGGUACUGAUUAUAAUAAGAAUGGACUCAGACGGUGAAAAACAUUUUCUCAUUAAAAUUCUUAACAAAAUAGAAGGUUUAACACUGACUGUCCUUCAUUCAAAUGAAAGAAAAGAUUUUCUGGAAUCUGAAGGUGUUUUAAGGGGUACAAGUUCCUGUGUAGUUGUACAUAAUCAAUAUAUUGGAGCAGAUUUCCCCUGGAGUAAUUUCUCAUUUGUGGUGGAAUACAAUUAUGUGGAAGACUCUUGUUGGACUAAACACUGCAAAGAGUUGAAUAUUCCUUACAUGGCCUUUAAAGUGAUUCUUCCAGACACAGUUUUAGAAAGAAGCACCUUGCUGGAUAGAUUUGGAGGUUUUCUUUUGGAAAUUCAGAUUCCAUAUGUGUUUUUUGCAUCUGAAGGACUUCUUAAUACUCCAGACAUACUUCAGCUGCUAGAAUCCAACUAUAACAUCUCACUAGUAGAGAGAGGCUGCAGUGAGUCAUUGAAACUCUUUGGAAGUUCAGAGUGUUAUGUAGUGGUGACAAUUGAUGAACACACUGCCAUAAUUUUGCAGGAUCUAGAAGAAUUGAAUUAUGAGAAGGCAUCAGACAAUAUCAUUAUGAGGCUGAUGGCAUUAUCAUUACAGUACAGAUAUUGUUGGAUAAUUUUAUAUACCAAAGAAACAUUAAAUUCAGAGUAUCUGCUUACAGAAAAGACACUUCAUCACCUAGCACUGAUUUAUGCAGCUUUGGUUUCAUUUGGGCUAAACUCUGAAGAACUGGAUGUAAAGACACCAAUUACAUUUCCGAAAUACAGCUGUGAAUAUUUCACUCACUAGACUAUAAGCUCCUUAAAGGUAAGGAAACAUAUUUAUUCUUUUUUUUUAUUCCUGGAACCUAGCACAAUGCCAGGUACAUAGUAGUCUCUUGAUAAAAAUUUGCUGUUGAUUUGAAUUUCUUGCUCAAAGACUGUCCAUAGCUUCCCACUUAAGUCAACAUAAAGUUCAAACUCAGCUGGAUUCAAACUCCUCCACAAUGUGGCCCUUAGUGAUUCCUUCUUUAACAUUAUUUUACUCACCAUUUACUGAGUAUGCCUCCAUACUGUCACCUCUCAGCCUUUGCACAAACAUGUCAUUCUGGCCUGCCUUCCCCCAGGAAUACUAUUCCCCGAUUCUCUUACCACUAGCUGUCAGAGUUCUACCUGUCUUUCACUGCCCAGUUCAAACGCGCUACCUCCUUUAAGAAACUUGCCCCACAUCACGCUACCUGACUUCAGACUAUACUACAAGGCUACAGUAACCAAAACAGCAUGGUACUGGUACCAAAACAGAGAUAUAGACCAAUGGAACAGAACAGAGCCCUCAGAAAUAAUACCACACAUCUACAACCAUCUGAUCUUUGACAAACCUGACAAAAACAAGAAAUGGGAAAAGGAUUCCUUAUUUAAUAAAUGGUGCUGGGAAAACUGGCUAGCCAUAGGUAAAAAGCUGAAACUGGAUCUCUUCCUUACACCUUACAGAAAAAUUAAUUCAAGAUGGAUUAAAGACUUAAAUGUUAGACCUAAAACCAUAAAAACCCUCGAAGAAAACCUAGGCAAUACCAUUCAGGACAUAGGCAUGGGCAACAACUUCACGAAUAAAACACGAAAAGCAAUGGCAACAAAAGCCAAAAUUGACAAAUGGGAUCUAAUUAAACUAAAGAACUUCUUCACAGCAAAAGAAACCUACCAUCAGAGUGAACAUGCAACCUACAGAAUGGGAGAACAUUUUUACAAUCUACCCAUCUGACAAAGGGCUAAUAUCCAGAAUCUACAAAGAACUUAAACAAAUUUACAAGAAAAAAUCAAACAACCCCAUCAAAAAGUGGGCAACAGAUAUGAACAGACACUUCUCAAAAGAAGACAUUUAUGCAUCCAACAGACACAAGAAAAAAUGCUCAUCAUCACUGGCCAUCAGAUAAAUGCAAAUCAAAACCACAAUGAGAUACCAUCUCACACCAGUUAGAAUGGCGAUCAUUAAAAAUCAGGAAACAACAGAUGCUGGAGAGAAUGUGGAGAAAUAGGAACACUUUUACACCGUUGGUGGGACUGUAAACUAGUUCAACCAUUGUGGAAGACAGUGUGGCGAUUCCUCUAGGAUCUAGAACUAGAAAUACCAUUUGACCCAGCCAUACCAUUACUGGGUAUAUACCCAAAGGAUUAUAAAUCAUGCUGCUAUAAAGACAUAUGCACACGUAUGUUUAUUGCUGCACUAUUCACAAUAGCAAAGACUUGGAACCAACUCAAAUGUCCAUCAAUGAUAGACUGGAUUAAGAAAAUGUGGCACAUAUACAUCAUGGAGUACUAUGCAGCCAUAAAAAAGGAUGAGUCCAUGUCCUUUGCAGGGACAUGGAUGAAGCUGGAAACCAUCAUUCUGAGCAAACUGUCACAAGGACAGAAAACCAAACACUGCAUGUUCUCACUCAUAGGUGGGAAUUGAACAAUGAGAACACUUGGACACAGGAUGGGGAACAUCACACACCGGGGCCUGUCGUGGGGUGGCGGGAGGUGGGAGUGAUAGCAUUAGGAGAUAUACCUAAUGUAAAUGACGAGUUAAUGGGGGCAGCACUCCAACAUGGCACAUGUAUACAUAUAUAACAAACCUGCACAUUGUGAACAUGUACUCUAGAACUUAAAGUAUAAUUAAAAAAAAAAAAAGGAGAGAAAAGAAACCUGCCCCAAUCCUACUCUCUCAGGAUGCAUCAUCUCUCCUCCCAUUCUCCUGCUGACAGUUCAUAUCUUAUUAUGGUAUGGGGAUAUUUAUUCAUAUAUCCUCCACCCUGAUGGGUAAGAAUGAUGCUCUUUUUAUUUGUAAAACCUAGCAGCUAGCAUAGUGCUUUGCACAAAGCAAAAACAUUCAAUAAAUGUCUACUAAGUGGAAUUCAAAGUACCACUUGCUAAGAAAAUCAACAAAUGAUCUGUUUGAACUGGAAUUCCAGAUAAUUUUGUUUCUGUGCUGCAUACUAAACAGAAAUAAAAUUCUUAGAAAAGUUACCUAAAGUGAAUGACAAAUGUAAAUUUGUCUCUAGUGAGGUCUUACCACUUAUUUAGCUUCUUCUCUUCCCAGCUCAGGGUAAACCAUUACAGGCAAAAUAUGCUUUAGAAAGUUUUUUUCCUCUAUGCAUGGGGCAUAUGAUACCAGUGAGUGAUACUAUAUUCAAAUACAGCAACAUGGCCCAUGGAGGGCAUGAUCCAAAUAAGGCAUUUGGGGAUGAAAUAGGAGUACCGCCUAGGAACAAUCCAUUCCAAACAAGUCUAUUUCCACCUGGAUCAAACUAUUCUAAAAGCUUUUCAGGUUUUACAUAAUAAUCUAAAAAGCAGGUCAUUUUUUCAAUGGACAUUGAGAGGCAACUAUGGUCAAUUUGCUCUUACUCUAUUAUCAGUAUGUCCUCAGUACUCAUAAGCCUCCUGUUUUCCUGACUUGAUGACAUUGUUGUAUUAAAGGAGGCUCCCUGGACUCAUAUUAUUUUAGAACAUAUUGUUGCUUUACCUUACUUUAUUUAGUAGCAUGGCUUUUGAUCUCUUAGAGCACAUCAGGACCAUUAGCACCUUUUUAUUUUCAGGCAUCUGAAGAACUUGAAAAUCAAGGAAGUAUUAGGAAGUUUAAGAACAUUUUCUUAAAUUAAAAGAAAAUACUGCUACUAGUGUUAUGCUAAGUGUUAUUCCAAUUUUUUAAAAGUUCUGUAAUUUUCUUAUGAACCAUCUUUGCAGGAAAAUGCAUAAAUACACACAUGCAAAAUUUUGCAAACAAAUUAAGUAGGUUCCUGAAUUCCCAAAUCUAGCCAUGAGCCCCAGAAUUCCUGCCCUAAUAAAUUAAUUGUCAUUAUCGCCAUCAUAAAAUUAUGGCUUUUAACCCUUUUCCCAUUUGCCCUGAGAAUCCUCACCAGCCAGGCUUGUUGCUGCAGUGUUUACCCUGAGACAACUUUGCCACGAAAUAUCUCGUUUUUAUUAUUGUUUUUGCAUCGCUGUAGCAUAUCAACUUUGGAAACAAAAGAUAUCUUUCUAUUUAUAGCAUUCUAUUUUUAGUAGUGGUAUUUCCAUUACAAAAUAUAGUAAUUCUCAGUCCCUGAAAAUGUCAAAUCCUAGAAAACAUAGUAUUCCUACUCGUGAUGUUAACAUCAUUCUCAAACAGUUGUUGGCUGAAGACUCCAUUGAUGAAUCUGAUUUUUCUGAAAUAGAAAAUUCUGAUGAUUCAGAUGAUUCUGAUGUUAUUUCUGUUUAGAAAUAACUCCAAGCACAGUUUUUAUAUUUUAUUUUCACAUCGAAAAUCAGUCAGAUUUGCUUCAGCCUCAAAGAGCGUGUUUAUGUAAAAUUAAAUGAGUGCUGUACUUUUUUUUUCUAAAUGGGAAAAGGGUUAAAAUAAAGUUUAUAUUUAAAUGAAAGUGUCAUAUCUUCUCAAAACACCCAAAACUAGCAAUAAAGUACAUUUGGAAUUGAACAAUAUAUUUCUGUGUAUUCUCCCUAUAUAAUGUAAUUUAAAGAAAAUCCUUUAAAAUGCAUAUACUCCCCAGGUGUGUACUAACCGUUUUGUAUUUGCUAUUCUUAUAAAAGAAAAAAAGUCAUAAUUAUUUUGUGAGAUUUCUACAGUUUACUAAAUUUCCACUAUAGUACAGGAUAUUUAUUUUCCAGGAUAUGAUUAUUUGGGGCAGUAUUUCUCUGUUCACGUUAAACUGCUAACUCAUGAACUAUCUUUCCUUCAAUCAAAUUUAAAAGAUGAAGAAGAAAAGAAAGAAAUGAAAGCAGAAAAAGAAGGUUGACAUUUCAGAAGAGAGAAGGGCAUGGAGGAAAACAGUGUCAGACAGGAAACAGAGGAUAUUAUGAAAUUAUUUUUUCUGUACUUUUUUUCCUUACUACUGUGCUAAUGGGAAAAAAUUAUUUUUUAGAAUUAAAUUUAAUAUACACAAACACCACAUUUUUGGCAGGGGUAUCUUAGAAUCAGUAAGCCAAUAUUAGAUGAGCAAUUCCCAAAAUGCUGGGAAUGAUGACUACUCUAAAUCAAAACCUUAUUUUUUCUUUUUUGAAUACAACAUCAAAUUCAUUUAUAAGUAUCCUUAUUUUUUAACUUUGUCUUUGAAAAAUCUUGCACUAUAUUUUUAAAAUUCUUAUUUUAAUUGACAACUAUUAGGUUUAACUUUUGGAAACAGCAAAAUAGUAAUAUUACUAGUGAUAUUCAAAUUGCUGAUUUUUCUAAUAUAGUUGAAAUAUAACACUAUAUUUUAAUGACUCUGUUAAUAAAUGCCAAAUGAAAUGAAAAUGAUUUAGUUCCAAAAAUUAAAAAUACAAGGAUAUCACAUUUAAAUAAGGAAUGAAAAUUGGUUAUCCUCAUAAAUAAAAUGUCCUGGACAUAGAUAAACCAAUAGUUUCUAUCUAAAAUUAGAUAGAAUCUGCUGUUGUUUAAUUUUAUCUUCUAAUUACAAACUGUUUAAAAAAUAUUAUAUUUUGCUUCCUAGUAUUUCCUAUAAUCUAACAUAAAAAAUAUUUUUUAGCUUAUAAUUGCCCCAGGAGUAGAAGCAACUGCCUUGAUAAUUCGACAAAUUGCUGACCACAGUUUAAUGACCUCAAAGAGAGAUCCUCAUGAAUGGUUGGAUAAAUCCUGGCUUAAAGUUUCACCAUCUGAGGUAUAUUUUCUAAAUGUGUAAAAUAGAUAAUUGCAAAGCAAAUAUAAAAACCUGUAUUUGAAUUUACUUUCUGGUAACAUUUUUCCCCCAAAUGUCUCAAAUUGAGUGGUAGGUGCAAUAACAAAAGUUUUAAUCUGCUGCAACGAGUAGAAUAAAAUGGAUCACUUUCGAAAGACUACUGACUAUUAAACUCUUUUCUAGGAAGAAAUGUACUUACUUGUAGAAUAAAAUGGCUCACUUUCAAAAGACUACUGACUGAUUAUUUCUUAAACUCUUUUCUAGGAAGAAAUGUACUUACUUGAUUUUCCAUGUAUUAACCCAUUGGUGGCUCAGCUCAUGCUAAAUAAAGGACCUUCACUGCAUUGGAUAUUAUUAGCAACUCUGUGUCAACUUCAGGAACUCCUACCUGAAGUCCCAGAAAAAGUGUUAAAGGUUAGUUAUUUGAGAUCUGUACUAUGAUAUGAAUUUAUUUCCUUUCGAUUUGAGUAUCUAUUUUUACAAUAGGAUUUUUAAAAUGAAGGUAUCCAAGUUUAAUUGUUUUGGACUUCAAAUAGCAAGGAAAUAAUUUACUUGAACUAAAUUUCAUAUAGACGUUUCAUUAGCUAUCAAUUAUACAUUUUAUUUUAUUUUUUAUUUUAUUUAUUUAUUUUUCCAGGCUGGAGUGCAAUGGUACAAUCUCAGCUCACUGCAACCUCCACCUCCCAAGUUCAAGAGAUUUUCCUGCCUCAGCCUCCCAAGUAGCUGGGAUUAUAAGUAUACAUCACCAUGCCUGGCUAAUUUUGAUUUUUUUUUUUUUUUUUUUUUUUUUUGUAGAAACGGGGUUUCACCAUCUUGGUCAGUCUGGUCUCAAACUCCUGACCUCAGGUGAUCCACCCACCUUGGCCUCCCAAAGUGCUGGGAUUACAGUAUUUUUUUCUUUUUUUUUGAGAUGGAGUCUCCCUCUGUCACCCAGGCUGGAGUGCAAUGGCUUGAUCUCGGCUCACUGCAGUCUCCAGCUCCUGGGUUCAAGCAAUUCUCGUGCCUCAGCCUCCCGAGCAGCUAGGACUGCAGUUGUGCACCACCACACCUGGUUAAGUUUUGUAUUUUUAGUAGAGACAGGGUCUUACCAUGUUGGCCAGGCUGGUCUCAAACUCCUGACCUCAAGUGAUCUAACUGCCUUGGCCUCCCAAAGUGCUAGGAUUACAGGCAUGAGCCAUAAACCCCAGCCUAUAUUAUACAUUCUAAAGCUAUUUUAUACAGAUAAAUUCAAUAUAGUCAGCUUUAAAUCAUUUUGGAAUAUUAUUGUGCUCAUAGAAAAUUCAGUUAUAUACCCUAUUCACAUGUAUUUACGUUACCUCUUCCAAACAGUCCUAACAUACCCUUAAUUCUAGCUGUAAAGAUAACUUUAGCCUUACUGGUAAUAUUUUAAAAUUCUUAUCAAGGAAAUAGUAUUCAUGUAUGAAUUGUAUAACUAAAAUUCUAUUGUAUUUGCUGUGAGCCUAAAAUUGUUCUGAAAAAUAGACUAUUAAAAAUUCUAUUACAAGUGAUUAGAAAAUAAGUAUGAAUUACAAUGAAUUUUUCUUUUAAUAGAGCCUAAUGAUUUCAUGUUCUUAAUACCUGGAUCAAUGUAAUAUCUAUGAAUAGACUACCUAUUUAUAUUUUGCCUUCUUUCCAUAUAGAUAAGCAUCAUUAUUUAUAUUUACUAAACUGACAUUUGCAUUAUAUUAAUUCAUUUUUUAGCAUUUUUGUAGCAUCACUUCCCUAUUCAAGAUUGGUUCUUCUUCCAUAACAAAAUCACCGCAAAUUUCGUCACCUCAGGAAAAUAGGAAUCAGAUUAGUACCUUGUCUUCUCAAAGUUCAGCUUCUGAUUUAGACUCUGUCAUUCAAGAACAUAAUGAAUAUUAUCAGUAUUUAGGAUUAGGAGAGACAGUGCAGGAAGACAAAACCACCAUUUUGAAUGACAACUCUUCCAUUAUGGAACUAAAAGAAAUCUCAAGUUUUUUACCACCUGUGACUUCAUACAAUCAGACCAGCUACUGGAAAGACUCCAGCUGUAAAUCUAAUAUAGGGCAGAAUACUCCUUUUCUAAUUAAUAUAGAAUCAAGGAGACCGGCUUAUAACUCCUUUCUAAACCACAGUGAUUCAGAGUCAGAUGUCUUUUCUUUGGGUCUAACACAAAUGAACUGUGAAACUAUAAAAUCACCAACUGACACUCAGAAGAGAGUGUCAGUUGUCCCCCGUUUUAUAAAUUCUCAGAAAAGGAGAACACAUGAAGCAAAAGGUUUCAUAAAUAAAGAUGUAUCGGACCCUAUCUUUUCACUAGAGGGCACUCAAUCUCCUCUUCAUUGGAACUUUAAGAAAAAUAUAUGGGAACAAGAGAAUCACCCGUUCAACUUACAAUAUGGUGCACAGCAGACUGCAUGUAACAAAUUGUACUCUCAGAAAGGUAAUUUAUUCACUGAUCAGCAAAAAUGUCUAUCAGAUGAGUCUGAAGGCCUCACAUGUGAAAGUUCAAAAGAUGAGACUUUCUGGAGAGAAUUACCAUCUGUCCCCAGUUUGGAUUUAUUUCGUGCUUCUGAUUCUAAUGCAAAUCAAAAAGAAUUCAACAGCCUUUAUUUCUACCAAAGAGCUGGAAAAAGUUUAGGACAGAAAAGGCACCAUGAAUCUUCAUUUAACUCAGGAGACAAGGAAUCAUUAACAGGUAACACUAUCCAAUAGUUGAUAAAACUACUCUCAAAUUUAAUUUUAAAAGAUAAAAUCAUCUCCAAAUUUAACAUUUUUUUUGUUUUAAUUACUACAUUUAAAAAACUUCUCUAAUAACUGUUGGGUAAAAGAGAAAAUCUAAACUCUAAAAUAAAUGCAGAGAAAAUAUAUUGUGUUAAAUUAUUAUAACCUUAAGUGGACUAAGCAUUCAACUUAAGAAGUUAAAAAUAAAAGCAGUGCAACUCUAAGUAAAGCAGGAGACUAAAAUCAACAAAGAUUAAACAGAGGAAUCAGUGAAUUAGAAAAUUAACCUCUUUGUGGAGCAGGUAUAUUUAACUGACUAACGUUUAUUAAAAGAGCCUAAUUAGGUGCCAGUCUCCAUUCUAAGUGCUUUAUUGGAUUAUUUACUUUAAUUCUAACAAUUCUAUUAAAUAGGCAGUAUUAUUAGCUCCAUUCUGGUGGAUGUUUUUGAGUUGUCUGAACAUUUAAGCAUAUCAAAUUUUUAAAAGCACAAUUUAAUUUUCUUGUUUCUAGUGAUUCUAGCUUUUCUUUCAGUGUCAUUUCUUACUGCAUUGGCCCAAGCAUCUAAAACAAAAUAUUAAGUUCUAACAGCCGUACAAAGGUGGCCUUCCCCAGGAUAGGAGAAAAAGGGGAGGGCGGGGGGAAGCUUAAGUUUCAAACUUCUCUUUUUCAUAGGUUUUUUUGUGAGGCCUGAGAGGGGCCAAGAAAAUCUUGUAUUUUUUGUUUUGUUUUAAAAAGGGCUCCCAAAUUGUAUAAGCUACAGGACUUGUAAUGCUUGGAUUUGCUCUUAUUUAAUACUUACAACUUGUUUUGUUCCUCACUUUAAUGGGAAGUAUUCUGUGUCUAGUUUUGUAAAAACUUCUGUGAAAAAUAGAUGCUGAAUUUAUUCAAACUCAUUUUAGUACAUAUUGGGAAAAAUCAAAUGUGUUUUCUCUACUGACCUAUUCAUGUCAAAGAUUAUAUUUACAGGUUUACUAAUAUUAAAAUAUCUAUGCCAUUUCUGUGAUAAACAUAACUGGUUUUUGAGGGGUGAUUCUUUAUUUUUAUAUUUUUGUUUUAUUUAAUAUUUCAUGCUACCUUGUCUAAGAGAUUUUUUGUUUCUUUAAGACAAGGUCUCCCUCUGUAGCCCAGGCUGGAGUGCAGUGGCAUGAUUGGUUCACUGCCACCCCCACCUUUCGGGCUCAACCGAUCCUCCCAUCUUAGCCUCCCAAGUAGCUGGGAUUACAGGCAUGCACCACCAUGCCUGGCUAAUUCAUUUCUAUUUUUAGUAGAGACAGGGUUUUGUUAUGUUGUCCAGGCUGAUCUCGAACUCCUCGGCUCAAGUAAUCUACCCGCCUUGGCCUCCCAAUGUGCUGGGAUUACAGGAGUGAGCCACCUGGCCCGGCCUAAGAGAUUCUUUUAAUAUGCUGUUAAAUAUGGUAGCUAAUAUUUAUGAUUUUCAUGUCUACAUUCAUGAUAUUAGAUUGUGUUCUUUAUUUGUGCCUUAUCACAUUUGGACAUAAAAGUUAUGCUAACUUCAUAAACUGGAUGAAAAUUUCAUAUUUUUCUACUCUGAAACAAAAUACACAUGUGAAUUACUAUAUGUUCUUGAACACAGGGCACUCCAAUAUAUAACCUCCCAUUUUCCAAUGAGAAGACCCAGAAGUCAUUUUUAAAUAAAUUCUAACAUUAAAUGUUAGAAAAAGCUUAAAGCUUUUAGGUAUAUGAGUAGAAUAGUCAAACAGCUACCUAUAUUUUAAUUCAUUAAUUUAGUUAUAUAUUUUUAAAUCACAUACUCUAUAAAAUAAUAUCAGUUUAGAAAUAUUAAUUUCUUCCAAUUUCCAAGUUAUUUCCAUGAAAUAAUUUUAUUCAAACAGUUCACAUGACUCUUUGAUACUAGUAUCUACAUUCAAUAUGGCAAAUUUUAUUUAAAUUAAAAAAAAUUUAUUUUUCCAUAGUACAUCAUUACCUCCAAAUACAUUGUUUAAGAUACAACACUUUUUGAAUUAAUAUUGGCACAGCCCUGGAAAAUUUAUCCAAAGCCAUUAGCAUAACCCAUAACCUCAAGAUAAUUUUCCAUUUGUCCCGAAGUGUAUAUAUGGGAUCUCUAUGAUAUAAUUACUUACUACAUUGCUUUAUUUUUAUUUUUUGGCAUGUCUGUUUGACAAAAUACAUUGCUUUUUAAAAUAAUAAUAAUAAUUAUUAUUAUUAUUAUUAUUGACAGAGUCUUGCUCUGUCACCCAGGCUGAAUCAUCCCUCCUCCACCUCUUGAGUAGCUGGGACGAAAGGUACGCACCACCACACCCAGCUAAUUUUUGUAUUUUUUGUAGAGGCAAAGUCUUGCCAUGUUGCCCAGUCUGGUCUCAAACUCUUGGGCUCAAGCAAUCCGCCUGCCUCAGCCUUCCAAAGUGCUGGGAUUACAGGUGUGAACUACUGCACCCCACCCUGCCUUUUAAACUUUUAAAUAAUGGUACCCUAACUCUUGGCAAUUAUGAGAUUAUAUCCCCAGGGAUAAUUAUUAAAACUGUUUUAUAAUUUUUAGUUUUCCAUUUUACUGAUUUCAUAAUCAGCCUCUGUAAGUAUCCAAAUCUAGGAUUUUUCACGUUAAUGUAUCAUAUUUUAAAAAGCCAUAUAAGGUGAGUUCUUAUAUAAUCACCACCUAUCAUUCAUCAGGGCUCAGAAUAAAUUUCACAUUACAGCUGUGGGUCAAGGAUCAAGCUAUGAGGGAAAACUUAAAAGCAAGAGUAUUGAAAAUGGCAUGUUAAAGACUCUAGAAUGGAAGCUGAAUAUGAGCUACUAAUACCAUUUUUAAAUAUGGUAUUUUAAUUUUUAUUUUUUUCUUAAUUGAUCUAUUAUAAAUUUUUUCUUUGAGCCAAGAGUGGGGUUUUUCUCAUGUUGUUGGUUUUUUUGAACUUUUGUUAUUUCUGACAACUGCAUUGUUAUCAGUUUAUUAUUUACUCCUUCCACUUAUUAAUGAUGAUUCUUUAUCUGACUUGGCAAGGAUAUAGUGAAUUUUGCUCAUAAUGUCCAAAAUGCUGGUAAUCUCUUCAAAACUGUUUUCAUCUGUGAAUGUACUUGGGACACUUUGUAUUGGUUAACUGGAAAUUUGUAUGUGCUUUAUAAUUGCACAUGUGGAUACUAAUAUAGGGAUAACUAUAUAUGGAUAUCCAUAUAUAAAUAAUAUAUGGAUAAUAAAUUGGAGUUAUUAAAUAGGUGCAAAAUAUACAUUUAUUUCAUGGGAAAGCUUCCUGGCAGCUAUAGAAAAAGAAAUUUAAGCAUUUUUAGAAAUUUUAGAAUUGGCUGUGAGAGAUUGAUAUCCAGAAAAAAACAUUGUUUCUAUCACAUUGGUAGCUUAAAAUCAGCCAUGGUGGGUGUCUUCAUACCACAAAAAUUUGCAGAUGCUACAAACCAGGCCUUUCCUUGUUUCGAGAGCUGGUUGUUAAACGUUUACCAGAAUGCUACUGGUAGUCCAGGCUCUCCCACAGCUUUACAGUGAAGAACCAAGGUCCUGUCGUCAUUAAUAUUCCCUGUAUUUCAUCUAAUUGUUUACUUAAGGAUUCUUUAGCUCCUUAAUUGGAGUUAAAGAUUUGUUUUCCAGACAUGCCUUUAAAGACAUGAAUUUACAGAUAGAUUCCUAAACACAUAACCUCUCCCUGAAACGAAAUAUGUCCUUAGUGAAAAUGAUAUCCCCCUAAAGGGUGUAUGUUCAUGAGAAGAAAAUUAGCCCAAGUGAAAAAAAGCCACAGUCAGGAAUAGGAAGGGCAAACUGGAAAAGAAAAAAGAAAAAAAAAAAGAAGAAGAAGAAAAACCGGACAGAAUUGUAUACACUCUCACCACAAAGAUGGAUACAAGGUACACGGAAACCAGGCAAUAUGUCUUUGUUUUAGGUUCAAAGUCUGUCAAAAUGAGCCUCUAACUUAUAUCCUAAUUAAUGAGGACUUAUUGGAAACUUUCAAGAAUUAGGAAGCCCGGCCUGAGGUGCUUCCCAAACCAUUUUGGGUUGUUUUUACUUAAAAAUGUUAGAAGAGAAUUUAGAGAUUAUGAAUUAUAACUUUUCAUUUCACAGAAGAGAAAAUUGAAACCAAGGGAGAUUUAAGUAUUUGUACAAGGCAUGAGCAUAAAAAUAUAUGCAUUUAUCACUAAUUUUUAAUACCGGGCCAUUAGGUACAGAGGCAUUUAUGUUAAAAACAUACUUUUUAAUAGUUAUUAUUUUAUCCCAGUUUGGAAAUUUUGACACUUUUUAGGUAGAUGAUGAAGACACAAAAUCCGUUUGAAUAGUGAGGAAAACAUACCUAUACUUCAGCCGGGCAUGGUGGCUCAUGCCUGUAAUCCCAGCACUUUGGGAGGCCGAGGCAGGUGGAUCACCUCAGGUCAGGAGUUUGAGACUAGCCUGCCCAACAUGGCAAAACCCUGUCUCUACUAAAAAUACAAAAAAUUAGCCGGGCGUGGUGGCAGGUGCCUGUAAUCCCAGCUGCUCGGGAGGCUGAGGCAGGAGAAUCGCUUGAACCCAGGAGGCAGAUGUUGCAAGUGAGCCGAGAUUGCGCCACUACACUCCAGCCUGGGCGACAAGGGCAAAACUUCAUCUCAAAAAAGAAAAAAAAAAAAAAAAGGAAAAGAAAAAACCUAUACUUUACUAUUGUAAGCAAUAAAAUGGUUUUCCUUUUUCUCCUUUUAACAGGUUUUAUGUGCUCACAACUACCACAAUUCAAAAAACGACGUCUAGCAUAUGAAAAAGUCCCUGGUAGAGUUGAUGGGCAGACUCGGCUGAGGUUUUUUUGAAGGAGGAGAAGAGCAAUGUUACAUGCCAUAUUCCACUGUUUUUGAUGCUAAUCCACUAGCGCAAUUAUUUAGAUUUGCUCAUACACUAAAGAAAACACAAUUGUUCAUAUAUGUCUCAGUAUUUCUGUAUUAAAUAUUCAUAAUAUGUA